ACUCCAUGUGAUGUUUGCUUGGUUGCCUGUUCCCUUUUCUACCUGCAGAGCACGGUUCCCAUAAGGGCGGCGAGAUCAGCCUCCUGUCUCAUCUGGAAGACCACCACUCUGGGGUCUCAGAGGAAUGAUGGAAGCCUUGGGGUUUCUAAAAUUGGAAGUGAAUGGCCCCAUGGUGACGGUGGCCCUGUCAGUGGCUCUCUUGGCCCUCCUGAAAUGGUACUCCACAUCAGCAUUCUCAAGACUGGAGAAGUUAGGCCUCAGACAUCCCAAGCCUUCUCCUUUCAUUGGAAACUUGACAUUUUUCCGCCAGGGUUUUUGGGAAAGCCAAAUGGAGCUCAGAAAGCUGUAUGGACCUCUGUGUGGGUACUAUCUUGGUCGUCGGAUGUUUAUUGUUAUUUCUGAGCCAGACAUGAUCAAGCAGGUGUUGGUUGAGAACUUCAGUAACUUUACCAACAGAAUGGCGUCGGGUUUGGAGUUCAAGUCGGUAGCCGACAGCGUUCUGUUUUUACGUGACAAAAGAUGGGAAGAGGUCAGAGGUGCCCUGAUGUCUGCUUUCAGUCCUGAAAAGCUGAACGAGAUGGUUCCCCUCAUCAGCCAAGCCUGCGACCUUCUCCUGGCUCAUUUAAAACGCUAUGCGGAAUCUGGGGACGCAUUUGACAUCCAGAGGUGCUACUGCAAUUACACCACAGAUGUGGUUGCCAGCGUCGCCUUUGGCACCCCGGUGGACUCCUGGCAGGCCCCUGAGGAUCCCUUUGUGAAACACUGCAAGCGUUUCUUCGAAUUCUGCAUCCCCAGACCUAUCCUGGUUUUACUCUUAUCAUUUCCAUCCAUAAUGGUCCCACUGGCCCGGAUUUUGCCCAAUAAGAACCGAGACGAACUGAAUGGCUUUUUUAACAAACUCAUUAGGAAUGUGAUUGCCUUGCGGGACCAGCAAGCUGCCGAAGAGAGGCGGAGAGACUUCCUCCAAAUGGUCCUGGAUGCCCGACAUUCUGCAAGUCCCAUGGGCGUGCAAGACUUUGACAUCGUCAGAGACGUUUUCUCCUCUACUGGGUGCAAGCCGAACCCUUCCCGGCAACACCAGCCCAGCCCUAUGGCCAGGCCUUUGACUGUGGAUGAGAUUGUGGGCCAGGCCUUCAUCUUCCUCAUCGCUGGCUAUGAAAUCAUCACCAACACACUUUCUUUUGCCACCUACCUACUGGCCACCAACCCUGACUGCCAAGAGAAGCUUCUGAGAGAGGUAGACGUUUUUAAGGAGAAACACAUGGCCCCUGAGUUCUGCAGCCUCGAGGAAGGCCUGCCCUAUCUGGACAUGGUGAUUGCAGAGACGCUGAGGAUGUACCCGCCAGCUUUCAGAUUCACACGGGAGGCAGCUCAGGACUGCGAGGUGCUGGGGCAGCGCAUCCCCGCAGGCGCUGUGCUAGAGAUGGCCGUGGGUGCCCUGCACCAUGACCCUGAGCACUGGCCAAGCCCGGAGACCUUCAACCCUGAAAGGUCCAAACUGAAUCCAGAGAUUUAGCAUUUCAGCAGCCCUGCAUGCAAGGAACAAGGCAAUUUCAAAUGAUUGUCUUCCAUUCAUUCAAGCCAGGACAUGGGAUACAGGAUUGUAUUUCAGGUCUGCACUGGAAAGUAACGGAACAUCAUUUCCUUUUUAAAAAACGGGCAUCUAUGCCAAAACAACAGCUUCAGCUGAUGUCUCCAUGAAUCUAAAUUCACGUGAUCCACUGGUUGACCUGGGUCCCCGCCUUCCACCACCUGGCUUUGGUUCAUUGUCUCCUUUCAUUUCUGGGCUCUGUGAUUGGAAACAUCUGAGCAGGCGGCCCACACUCUGGUCCUCAUCAGAACCAGUCAAUAUCCUGUGUGUGUGAUCUGGCAAGGGAAGGGCUGGCCCGGCACCAGUUGUGUUUUCACCUUUCAUGGCUCCAACUGAGUUCAGCCCAAGCCUACGACCCAGUCACUGGGAAAACGUGAGCAAUGGGAUCUACACAACAAUAUUCCACAGUCAGCAGCUCCUGAACGUGCCGCAGCCACAGGGCUUACAGCCUCACAAUAAAGCCCAGGGGUAGUAAAAAGUGAGCUCGCUGUUACAGAACAGUGAGUGCCACCUAGCUUCACUGUCAUGGGACACACGCUGCAGGCAAAUGCACUACUUGGUAGGAGAUUCAGCAGUUCUGAGGAAGGGCCUCCAGCUCUCCAGGUACUGCAGCUUCCAGUGGUUCAAGUGUCCAGUGCAGGGGCCUGCAAAGCAAACACGGGCAGGAGAGGGGCUGCCAGUGUGGCCCAAGAGACCUGCAGGGCAAGCCAGCAGGACACGCCCCCCAGGGAGGGCCCAGGAGGUGCUGAGGUGCCCGGUACCCUGCCAAGGAAGCAGGUGGCGGCUGGGUCAUCCUAUGGGAGGGGAGGUGGCGCCAUGGGCCCAGGUGAGGGUGAUCACCAAACCCUGGGGUUCAGGGAUGCCGUGUUUAGACUCUGAUUGUGGGUGGCGGUGAGUCUGUGGGCUUAUUAGCCACACACUGAAUUCCUAAGGAGAGGCAGGGAGGGAGCUGUGGACAUUCCAGGUGAUUCUGCGAAUUCAGCUCUGCCUCUGGGGCUGUGCAGGAAGACAGGAGGCCAGGAGCAGAGAGGGACUGAGGCUCAGGAAUGAGCAGCCAUCAGCUCCCAGAGCCUUGGAGACAUCCUUGUCUCAGAUGCAGGGGUGGCUCAGCUGGAGCACAGGGCUGCAGAGGGGAGGGAGCGGGUGUUCUGGGCCAGCCCUGACCACACGGACCUGCAGGUUCACGGCUGAGGCCCGGCAGCAGCACCGGCCCUUCACGUACCUGCCCUUCGGGGCCGGCCCACGGAGCUGCCUCGGGGUGCGUCUAGGGCUGCUUGAGGUCAAGUUGACACUGCUCCACGUGCUGCACAAGUUCCGGUUCCAAGCCUGCCCUGAGACCCAG